CCCGCUGAGCGUCGACACAGUCGCUGUUGGCCUGGUGUCCAGCGUGGUUGUCUAUCCCGUCUACCUGGCCAUCCUCUUUCUCUUCCGGAUGUCCCGGAGCAAGGUGGCUGGGAGCCUGAGCCCCACACCUGCCGGGCAGUAGGUGCUGGACAUCGACAGCUGCCUGGACUCGUCCGUGCUGGACAGCUCCUUCCUCACGUUCUCAGGCCUCCACGCUGAGGUGAGGGCUCUACUGGGGGUCCUGGGCUGGGCUGGGGGUCCUGCCGCCUUGGCGCAGCUUGGACUCCAGACACUGUGCACCUCUCAGCAGGCCUUUGCUGGACAGGUGAAGAGUGACUUGUUUCUGGAUGAUUCUAAGAGGUUGAUGGACGGAUGGCUACAUGGAUGUGAUGGAGAUGGUUUACUAUCGGGACCUUCCGCAUCCUGCUGAUGUUUUGUUGCUUAGGAUAUGAAUGGCUGAGCGGAGGCUGUACAACCUGGCACUCUGCUUGGGUUAUCAAUACUCUGGCUGACCAUCGUCAUCGUGGGACUGACUUUGGUGGAAGUCCUUGGUUACUUAUCAUUACUGUGUUUCUGAGAAGUUAUAAAUUUGCCAUCUCCCUCUGCACAAGUUACCUUUGUGUGUCUUUCCUGAAGACUAUCUUCCCAUCUCAAAAUGGACAUGAUGGAUCCACGGAUGUACAGCAGAGAGCCAGGAGGUCCAACCGCCGUAGACAGGAAGGAAUUAAAAUUGUCCUGGAAGACAUCUUUACUUUAUGGAGACAGGUGGAAACCAAAGUUCGAGCUAAAAUCCGUAAGAUGAAGGUGACAACAAAAGUCAACCGUCAUGACAAAAUCAAUGGAAAGAGGAAGACCGCCAAAGAACAUCUGAGGAAACUAAGCAUGAAAGAACGUGAGCACAGAGAAGAGGAGAGGCAGGUGUCAGAGGCAGAGGAAAAUGGGAAAUUGGAUAUGAAAGAAAUACACACCUACAUGGAAAUGUUUCAACGUGCGCAAGCGUUGCGGCGGCGGGCAGAGGACUACUACAGAUGCAAAAUCACCCCUUCUGCAAGAAAGCCUCUUUGCAACCGGGUCAGAAUGGCGGCAGUGGAGCAUCGUCAUUCUUCAGGAUUGCCCUACUGGCCCUACCUCACAGCUGAAACUUUAAAAAACAGGAUGGGCCACCAGCCACCUCCUCCAACUCAACAACAUUCUAUAAUUGAUAACUCCCUGAGCCUCAAGACACCUUCCGAGUGUGUGCUCUAUCCCCUUCCACCCUCAGCGGAUGAUAAUCUCAAGACACCUCCCGAGUGUCUGCUCACUCCCCUUCCACCCUCAGCUCUACCCUCAGCGGAUGAUAAUCUCAAGACACCUGCCGAGUGCCUGCUCUAUCCCCUUCCACCCUCAGCGGAUGAUAAUCUCAAGACACCUCCCGAGUGUCUGCUCACUCCCCUUCCACCCUCAGCUCCACCCUCAGCGGAUGAUAAUCUCAAGACACCUCCUGAGUGUGUCUGCUCACUCCCCUUCCACCCUCAGCGGAUGAUAAUCUCAAGAAACUAAGGAAGAAUAAAUAAAUAAUAUAAAAAUAAAAUGAAUACUGCAGUCCUUA